AGUUUCCCACAAGCCAGGCUGAUCCUUUUCUGUCAGUCCACUUCACCAAGCCUGCCCUUGGACAAGGACCCGAUGCCCAACCCCAGGCCUGGCAAGCCCUCGGCCCCUUCCUUGGCCCUUGGCCCAUCCCCAGGAGCCUCGCCCAGCUGGAGGGCUGCACCCAAAGCCUCAGACCUGCUGGGGGCCCGGGGCCCAGGGGGAACCUUCCAGGGCCGAGAUCUUCGAGGCGGGGCCCAUGCCUCCUCUUCUUCCUUGAACCCCAUGCCACCAUCGCAGCUGCAGCUGCCCACACUGCCCCUAGUCAUGGUGGCACCCUCCGGGGCACGGCUGGGCCCCUUGCCCCACUUACAGGCACUCCUCCAGGACAGGCCACAUUUCAUGCACCAGCUCUCAACGGUGGAUGCCCACGCCCGGACCCCUGUGCUGCAGGUGCACCCCCUGGAGAGCCCAGCCAUGAUCAGCCUCACACCACCCACCACCGCCACUGGGGUCUUCUCCCUCAAGGCCCGGCCUGGCCUCCCACCUGGGAUCAACGUGGCCAGCCUGGAAUGGGUGUCCAGGGAGCCGGCACUGCUCUGCACCUUCCCAAAUCCCAGUGCACCCAGGAAGGACAGCACCCUUUCGGCUGUGCCCCAGAGCUCCUACCCACUGCUGGCAAAUGGUGUCUGCAAGUGGCCCGGAUGUGAGAAGGUCUUCGAAGAGCCAGAGGACUUCCUCAAGCACUGCCAGGCGGACCAUCUUCUGGAUGAGAAGGGCAGGGCACAAUGUCUCCUCCAGAGAGAGAUGGUACAGUCUCUGGAGCAGCAGCUGGUGCUGGAGAAGGAGAAGCUGAGUGCCAUGCAGGCCCACCUGGCUGGGAAAAUGGCACUGACCAAGGCUUCAUCUGUGGCAUCAUCCGACAAGGGCUCCUGCUGCAUCGUAGCUGCUGGCAGCCAAGGCCCUGUCGUCCCAGCCUGGUCUGGCCCCCGGGAGGCCCCUGACAGCCUGUUUGCUGUCCGGAGGCACCUGUGGGGUAGCCAUGGAAACAGCACAUUCCCAGAGUUCCUCCACAACAUGGACUACUUCAAGUUCCACAACAUGCGACCCCCUUUCACCUACGCCACGCUCAUCCGCUGGGCCAUCCUGGAGGCUCCAGAGAAGCAGCGGACACUCAAUGAGAUCUACCACUGGUUCACACGCAUGUUUGCCUUCUUCAGAAACCAUCCUGCCACCUGGAAGAACGCCAUCCGCCACAACCUGAGUCUGCACAAGUGCUUUGUGCGGGUGGAGAGCGAGAAGGGGGCUGUGUGGACCGUGGAUGAGCUGGAGUUCCGCAAGAAACGGAGCCAGAGGCCCAGCAGGUGUUCCAACCCUACACCUGGCCCCUGACCUCAAGAUCAAGGAAAGGAGGAUGGACGAACAGGGGCCAAACUGGUGGGAGGCAGAGGUGGUGGGGGCAGGGAUGAUAGGCCCUGGAUGUGCCCACAGGGACCAAGAAGUGAGGUUUCCACUGUCUUGCCUGCCAGGGCCCCUGUUCCCCCGCUGGCAGCCACCCCCUCCCCCAUCAUAUCCUUUGCCCCAAGGCUGCUCAGAGGGGCCCCGGUCCUGGCCCCAGCCCCCACCUCCGCCCCAGACACACCCCCCAGUCGAGCCCUGCAGCCAAACAGAGCCUUCACAACCAGCCACACAGAGCCUGCCUCAGCUGCUCGCACAGAUUACUUCAGGGCUGGAAAAGUCACACAGACACACAAAAUGUCACAAUCCUGUCCCUCACUCAACACAAACCCCAAAACACAGAGAGCCUGCCUCAGUACACUCAAACAACCUCAAAGCUGCAUCAUCACACAAUCACACACAAGCACAGCCCUGACAACCCACACACCCCAAGGCACGCACCCACAGCCAGCCUCAGGGCCCACAGGGGCACUGUCAACACAGGGGUGUGCCCAGAGGCCUACACAGAAGCAGCGUCAGUACCCUCAGGAUCUGAGGUCCCAACACGUGCUCGCUCACACACACGGCCUGUUAGAAUUCACCUGUGUAUCUCACGCAUAUGCACACGCACAGCCCCCCAGUGGGUCUCUUGAGUCCCGUGCAGACACACACAGCCACACACACUGCCUUGCCAAAAAUACCCCGUGUCUCCCCUGCCACUCACCUCACUCCCAUUCCCUGAGCCCUGAUCCAUGCCUCAGCUUAGACUGCAGAGGAACUACUCAUUUAUUUGGGAUCCAAGGCCCCCAACCCACAGUACCGUCCCCAAUAAACUGCAGCCGAGCUCCCCA